GUGGGCGCCUGCGAGGGCUUGGGAGAGCAAGCCGCGGAGAGGUGAGUGGGCCGCUUUUCUACGGGAACUGGCCUGAACUCGGCCGUACGGGCUCCCCAGUAACCGACCUUUGGCCAAAGUGUGGAUGGAGUAGGAGGAGUUUUGAAGCCGUCCUUCGAAGCCUUUCUGCCUCGGGGUCUCAGAGUCCCACGGGUGCCCAAAGUCUGGGCUUGAGGCCUGCAGAGGAGGCGAAGGGGCCUUAUUCCUGGCUUCUUCACUGCGUUUUCUCUGAACAGACAUGAACUUGAAGCCACCAUGGGAGAUGAAGAUUGGGAAGCAGAAAUCAACCCUCAUAUGUCUUCCUAUGUUCCCAUAUUUGAGAAGGAUAGGUAUUCUGGAGAAAAUGGAGACAAUUUUAACAGGACUCCAGCUUCAUCAUCAGAAAUGGAUGAUGGACCUUCUCGAAGAGAUCAUUUCAUGAAAAGUGGAUUUGCCUCUGGGCGGAAUUUUGGAAACAGAGAUGCUGGUGAGUGUAAUAAGCGAGAUAAUACAUCCACAAUGGGUGGUUUUGGAGUUGGAAAGAGUUUUGGAAACAGAGGUUUUUCAAACAGCAGGUUUGAAGAUGGUGAUAGCUCUGGUUUCUGGAGAGAGUCUAGUAAUGACUGCGAAGAUAAUCCAACACGGAACAGAGGGUUUUCCAAGAGAGGCGGCUAUCGAGAUGGAAAUAAUUCAGAAGCUUCAGGGCCAUACAGAAGAGGUGGAAGAGGUAGUUUCCGAGGUUGCCGUGGAGGAUUUGGUCUAGGAAGUCCAAAUAAUGACUUAGACCCAGACGAAUGUAUGCAGCGCACUGGUGGCCUUUUUGGUUCUAGAAGACCAGUAUUAAGUGGCACAGGUAAUGGUGAUACUUCUCAAAGCAGAAGUGGCAGUGGAAGUGAACGAGGUGGUUACAAAGGUUUAAAUGAAGAAGUAAUAACAGGCUCUGGAAAGAAUUCUUGGAAGUCAGAAGCAGAAGGAGGAGAAAGUAGUGAUACUCAAGGACCAAAAGUGACCUACAUACCCCCUCCUCCACCUGAGGAUGAGGACUCCAUCUUUGCACAUUAUCAGACAGGCAUAAACUUCGACAAAUACGACACUAUUCUUGUGGAAGUGUCUGGACAUGAUGCACCACCAGCAAUUCUGACUUUUGAAGAAGCUAAUCUCUGUCAGACACUGAAUAACAACAUUGCUAAAGCUGGUUAUACUAAGCUUACUCCUGUGCAAAAAUACAGUAUUCCUAUCAUACUUGCAGGACGAGAUUUGAUGGCUUGCGCUCAAACAGGGUCUGGGAAGACUGCGGCUUUUCUCCUACCAAUUUUGGCUCAUAUGAUGCAUGAUGGAAUAACUGCCAGUCGUUUUAAAGAGUUGCAGGAACCAGAGUGUAUUAUUGUAGCACCAACUCGAGAAUUGGUCAACCAGAUUUAUUUGGAAGCCAGAAAAUUUUCUUUUGGGACUUGUGUAAGAGCUGUUGUUAUAUAUGGGGGAACCCAGCUGGGACAUUCAAUUCGACAAAUAGUACAAGGCUGUAAUAUAUUAUGUGCUACUCCUGGAAGACUGAUGGAUAUCAUAGGCAAAGAAAAGAUUGGUCUCAAACAGAUCAAAUACUUAGUUUUGGAUGAAGCUGAUCGCAUGUUGGAUAUGGGUUUUGGUCCAGAAAUGAAGAAGUUAAUUUCUUGCCCAGGAAUGCCAUCAAAGGAACAGCGCCAAACCCUUAUGUUCAGUGCAACUUUUCCAGAGGAAAUUCAAAGGUUGGCUGCAGAGUUUUUAAAGUCAAAUUAUCUGUUUGUUGCUGUUGGACAAGUGGGUGGAGCAUGUAGAGAUGUUCAGCAGACCGUUCUCCAAGUUGGCCAGUUCUCAAAAAGAGAAAAGCUCGUUGAAAUUCUGCGAAACAUAGGGGAUGAAAGAACUAUGGUCUUUGUUGAAACUAAGAAAAAAGCAGAUUUUAUUGCAACUUUUCUUUGUCAAGAAAAAAUAUCAACUACAAGUAUUCAUGGUGAUCGGGAACAGAGAGAGCGGGAGCAAGCUCUUGGAGAUUUUCGCUUUGGAAAGUGCCCAGUUCUUGUUGCUACUUCAGUAGCUGCCAGAGGGCUGGAUAUUGAAAAUGUGCAACAUGUUAUCAAUUUUGAUCUUCCUUCUACCAUUGAUGAAUAUGUUCAUCGAAUUGGGCGUACUGGUCGUUGUGGGAAUACUGGCAGAGCAAUUUCCUUUUUUGAUCUUGAAUCGGAUAACCAUUUAGCACAGCCUCUAGUAAAAGUAUUGACAGAUGCUCAACAGGAUGUUCCUGCAUGGUUGGAAGAAAUUGCCUUUAGUACAUACAUUCCUGGCUUCAGUGGUAGUACAAGAGGAAACGUGUUUGCAUCAGUUGAUACCAGAAAGGGCAAGAGCACUUUGAACACAGCUGGGUUUUCUUCUUCACAAGCUCCCAAUCCAGUAGAUGAUGAGUCAUGGGAUUAAAGCCAAAACAUCCUUCAAGUCUGUGGUUUUGAUGCAGAGAAGAAAAUAGUUUUGAUUUUUGAGUUUUUAACAGAAGUAUAAAACUUAACAUUCUCAUAGCUCCUGUCCUUGUAUUCUCACUCCUACACUUAAAAAAAAAAUCCUUACUGACUAGUUAUGUGAGAUGCUAAAACUUACAACAUUGCAGUUACUGAUACAAAUGGUGUUAACUGGGAAUAUUAAAGCAUUCUAAAUGUCUUUCUUAUUUCUGGUAUAUUCUUUAGGGGGCUUAGACAUGUUUAAUGUUUAAAUGCCAAGUCUUACUAUAGUGUUUAUUGAUCUUAUAAAACAAGCAAAUAGGAUAUGAUACACUUUUGGUUAAAAAUUACUGGGUCUCAUUUUUACUUGAGUCUUUAAAACAGUAGUGUGUCACUAUAAUGUGAUAAUCUUUAAGAGAAAGUAGAAUACUUAAGCCUUUCAAAGUGAUUUUGAUUUUUAGAUCAUCAGAUGUAUGAUGAAAAUGGUUAAAUGUUUGUGAUGGGAGCUCUGUACUCAAUGGCAUAACAAUGUUUAUUUUUAUAAUAUACAAUCUUUCCUUGAAAUAAAGGAUGAAACACUUUUCCCUUAAGUUUUCCAUC